GGUGGCCCGGACGGAAAAGAUACCUCGGCGGCGUGGGCCCGGCUCCCUGCUCCAGGACCUAGGGAUCUUGGCCUUCCACCCUCCUCCGAGCACCAGGACUCCCUCCAGUUCCGUACCCGAGGCCUCCGUGGUGAAGAGGUGCCGGACCCGAUGAGCUCGGGAGUCCACCAUCGCUCUGCAAGCCGCAGAGAGCAUCUGCUGCCGAGGCCAAUAGGAGCCGUGUGUACUCAAGACCCUAACCAGGAUCCUGCAGGUCCCGCCUCCGCAGCCCCACGGGGCUGCCGGCCCCCCCACCUCCCAUCGCGAGCCUGGCUGCGCCGGCGUGCUUGAGCCCGGUGACUGCAAGGCCCCGGGUCUCCCCUGCGCCUGCGCGGCGAGCAGCUGGCGGAACCGGCAUCUUCUGGCGCCAGCUUCCGGCUUAGCGGCUGAGCUUCAGGCUUGACGUCAGACCCAAGCCCCAGGUCGUGGGACGAUUUCUCCCGUUUUUGACUCCCUGGAACUGUAUUGCCUGCUUUACCUGCGUACAUGUUGAUUCUUUCUCAUGGCAACCCCGCAGGAAACCAUCAAGAUCUCAUUUUACAGCUGGGAUUCUCUGGUUCACAGAGGUAACGGAGCUUGCCCGAGGCCAGUUAAACGAGAAGAUUCAUCACCGCUUUGAUGGCUGCCUCACAAACUUCACAAACUGUUGCAUCUCACGUUCCUUUUGCAGAUUUGUGUUCAACUUUAGAACGAAUACAGAAAAGUAAAGGACGUGCAGAAAAAAUCAGACACUUCAGGGAAUUUUUAGAUUCUUGGAGAAAAUUUCAUGAUGCUCUUCAUAAGAACCACAAAGAUGUCACAGACUCUUUUUAUCCAGCAAUGAGACUAAUUCUUCCUCAGCUAGAAAGAGAGAGAAUGGCCUAUGGAAUUAAAGAAACUAUGCUUGCUAAGCUUUAUAUUGAGUUGCUUAAUUUACCUAGAGAUGGAAAAGAUGCCCUCAAACUUUUAAACUACAGAACACCCACUGGAACUCAUGGAGAUGCUGGAGACUUUGCAAUGAUUGCAUAUUUUGUGUUGAAGCCAAGAUGUUUACAGAAAGGAAGUUUAACCAUACAGCAAGUAAACGACCUUUUAGACUCAAUUGCCAGCAAUAAUUCUGCUAAAAGAAAAGACCUAAUAAAAAAGAGCCUUCUUCAACUUAUAACUCAGAGUUCAGCACUUGAGCAAAAGUGGCUUAUACGGAUGAUCAUAAAGGAUUUAAAGCUUGGUGUUAGUCAGCAAACUAUCUUUUCUGUUUUUCAUAAUGAUGCUGCUGAGUUGCAUAAUGUCACUACAGAUCUGGAAAAAGUCUGUAGGCAACUGCAUGAUCCUUCUGUAGGACUCAGUGAUAUUUCUAUCACUUUAUUUUCUGCAUUUAAACCAAUGCUAGCUGCUAUUGCAGAUAUUGAGCACAUUGAGAAGGAUAUGAAACAUCAGAGUUUCUACAUAGAAACCAAGCUAGAUGGUGAACGUAUGCAAAUGCACAAAGAUGGAGAUGUAUAUAAAUACUUCUCUCGAAAUGGAUAUAACUACACUGAUCAGUUUGGUGCUUCUCCUACUGAAGGUUCUCUUACCCCAUUCAUUCAUAAUGCAUUCAAAGCAGAUAUACAAAUCUGUAUUCUUGAUGGUGAGAUGAUGGCCUAUAAUCCUAAUACACAAACUUUCAUGCAAAAGGGAACUAAGUUUGAUAUUAAAAGAAUGGUAGAGGAUUCUGAUCUGCAAACUUGUUAUUGUGUUUUUGAUGUAUUGAUGGUUAAUAAUAAAAAGCUAGGGCAUGAGACUCUGAGAAAGAGGUAUGAGAUUCUUAGUAGUAUUUUUACACCAAUUCCAGGUAGAAUAGAAAUAGUGCAGAAAACACAAGCUCAUACUAAGAAUGAAGUAAUUGAUGCAUUGAAUGAAGCAAUAGAUAAAAGAGAAGAGGGAAUUAUGGUAAAACAACCUCUAUCCAUCUACAAGCCAGACAAAAGAGGUGAAGGGUGGUUAAAAAUUAAACCAGAGUAUGUCAGUGGACUAAUGGAUGAAUUGGACAUUUUAAUUGUUGGAGGAUAUUGGGGUAAAGGAUCACGGGGUGGAAUGAUGUCUCAUUUUCUGUGUGCAGUAGCAGAGAAGCCCCCUCCUGGUGAGAAGCCAUCUGUGUUUCAUACUCUCUCUCGUGUUGGGUCUGGCUGCACCAUGAAAGAACUGUAUGAUCUGGGUUUGAAAUUGGCCAAGUAUUGGAAGCCUUUUCAUAGAAAAGCUCCACCAAGCAGCAUUUUAUGUGGAACAGAGAAGCCAGAAGUAUACAUUGAACCUUGUAAUUCUGUCAUUGUUCAGAUUAAAGCAGCAGAGAUCGUACCCAGUGAUAUGUAUAAAACUGGCUGCACCUUGCGUUUUCCACGAAUUGAAAAGAUAAGAGAUGACAAGGAGUGGCAUGAGUGCAUGACCCUGGACGACCUAGAACAACUUAGGGGGAAGGCAUCUGGUAAGCUCGCAUCUAAACACCUUUAUAUAGGUGGUGAUGAUGAACCACAAGAAAAAAAGCGGAAAGCUGCCCCAAAGAUGAAGAAAGUUAUUGGAAUUAUUGAGCACUUAAAAGCACCUAACCUUACUAACGUUAACAAAAUUUCUAAUAUAUUUGAAGAUGUAGAGUUUUGUGUUAUGAGUGGAACAGAUAGCCAGCCAAAGCCUGACCUGGAGAACAGAAUUGCAGAAUUUGGUGGUUAUAUAGUACAAAAUCCAGGCCCAGACACGUACUGUGUAAUUGCAGGGUCUGAGAACAUCAGAGUGAAAAACAUAAUUUUGUCAAAUAAACAUGAUGUUGUCAAGCCUGCAUGGCUUUUAGAAUGUUUUAAGACCAAAAGCUUUGUACCAUGGCAGCCUCGCUUUAUGAUUCAUAUGUGCCCAUCAACCAAAGAACAUUUUGCCCGUGAAUAUGAUUGCUAUGGUGAUAGUUAUUUCAUUGAUACAGACUUGAACCAACUGAAGGAAGUAUUCUCAGGAAUUAAAAAUUCUAACGAGCAGACUCCUGAAGAAAUGGCUUCUCUGAUUGCUGAUUUAGAAUAUCGGUAUUCCUGGGAUUGCUCUCCUCUCAGUAUGUUUCGACGCCACACCGUUUAUUUGGACUCGUAUGCUGUUAUUAAUGACCUGAGUACCAAAAAUGAGGGGACAAGGUUAGCUAUUAAAGCCUUGGAGCUUCGGUUUCAUGGAGCAAAAGUAGUUUCUUGUUUAGCUGAGGGAGUGUCUCAUGUAAUAAUUGGGGAAGAUCAUAGUCGUGUUGCAGAUUUUAAAGCUUUUAGAAGAACUUUUAAGAGAAAGUUUAAAAUCCUAAAAGAAAGUUGGGUAACUGAUUCAAUAGACAAGUGUGAAUUACAAGAAGAAAACCAGUAUUUGAUUUAAAGCUAGGUUUCCUAGUGAGGAAAGCCUCUGAUCUGGCAGACUCAUUGCAGCAGGUGGUAAUGAUAAAAUACUAAACUACAUUUUAUUUUUGUAUCUUAAAAAUCUAUGCCUAAAAAGUAUCAUUACAUAUAGGAAAACAAUAAUUUUAACUUUUAAGGUUGAAAAGACAAUAGCCCAAAGCCAAGAAAGAAAAAUUAUCUUGAAUGUAGUAUUCAAUGAUUUUUUAUGAUCAAGGUGAAAUAAACAGUCUAAAGAAGAGGUGUUUUUAUAAUAUCCAUAUAGAAAUCUAGAAUUUUUACUUAGAUACUAAUAAAAUACAUUUAGAAACUUUUAAAGUCAUGAAAAAGCAUUAACCUUCUAAACAGUAUAUUCUAAAAAGUCAAAACGUUAACAAUAGUUUUUAUCUAAUAAAAGCACUGCAAGAAAAUAGGGUAGAAUUGUUACAGCUGGACUUGUAAAAAUAUGUCUUUUUACUCAGGGUUUAAAAUGUCCCAUUUAAAUAUGAAAUGUAAACAAAUUUGUUUUUUAAGGUUAAGGCCAAAUGUAACAAUAAAACCCUGUCGAUGGUUUUAGCUAAAUUAGAGGAAGUUGUAUGAGACUUAAUGAUCUAAAAACUUAAAAUUGAAUUGGUUUGAUUAAAAAUAAAGCUUGCAAUUUUAAAAGUAGCUCACAUUUAAUUUCUUGUGUGAAAUAGAACAUGCUUUAAAGGAAGUAUUUUUAUGUGAAUUUGCAUUCCAGUAUAAAUAGUAUUCACAAAAAAGAUUUUCCUAGAUUUUAUCUAUUGAAUAGGUGUCAAUAUGGCAUGCAUAUUGUAACUUUCAUUAGAAAUAAGUUGCUUUGACUUUUAAAAAUGACAUAGUUAGAUUAUUUAAAGUCAAUGUAUAUAGUAUAUAUUAUGUAUGGAUUUAUAUACCAAAUUUUGGAAUACAGCCUAUCUCAUGACCAUAUUGAAAUGUACGGAAUUUGAUCCAUGCGAUACUAUGUGUGCAUUAUUUGAAAGUUAUUGGAAAUUUUAUUCAAACCGUGGAACAAAUGUAUGUGAUUUUGUUAUACUUCUUAAUUUAAAUAAAAUAUUUAAUGCACUAUUAAAA